UUACAUCAGGGUUAAAAAAGCACAGGAAGUUUACGCACAGAGCAAAGCCAUUUGCUAGAAUUGGUUUUUAUCCUUCCAUUUCGAAAAUAAAGUUGCUGUUUGUGUUGGAGAUGCUGUCAUCAGAAUUCCGCGGCACAAAGAGAAAGAUACAAAAAUAUCUCUCUGACAUGUAACUUUCCCCCUUCUUCUAGCCCCUUGCUAGGAAUGCCAGAAGAGGAUCCCACGCUGACUGGAACCAUUAGGUCUUUUGUUUGAAUCCCAGUGAUCGAGAAAGAAAUGUGGUUCAUAAUCAGCUAGUAGUGGAGAAAAAAGGAACCCAAGGAGAUAGGAGAGCUGUUAAUUUCACUCGGGACAUUUCCUCGAGGCUAGUUUACUCGGAAAGCCUCAAUGUUCCCUGGUAGCUGCAGGAUCUACUUUGGGGGCUGCCAAGUUUCCUCUCUCAUUCUUUCUCCUGCCCCAAGAGCAGGCAGGAAGGAAAGUUCCUGGACUGAUACUCGUCUGUUUAGUAGGCGUGGGUCCUGGUUGAAGUCUGUCUAGGAAAACUCCUAAGUGUAGAAAUCUUCUUCGUAUUACCACUGUCUCUGCACUGAGAUUUGGGCUGCUUUGCUUCCAGCGUCACACAUCAUAACUGAGUGCAGUACCGGUUUGACUGUAUCUUCAAGUUAAGAGAAUUGCUGUAUUCCCCAAAAUAUCUUGGUCAUUUGAAAGUAAAGAGUUCUCGGCCGGGCACAGUGGCUCACGCCUGUAAUCCCAGCACUUCAGAAGGCAAAGAAAGAUAAAAACUCUCCAGAUGUCUUCCAGUAAUGUCGAAGUUUUUAUCCCAGUGUCACAAGGAAACACCAAUGGCUUCCCCGCGACAGCUUCCAAUGACCUGAAGGCAUUUACUGAAGGAGCUGUGUUAAGUUUUCAUAACAUCUGCUAUCGAGUAAAACUGAAGAGUGGCUUUCUACCUUGUCGAAAACCAGUUGAGAAAGAAAUAUUAUCGAAUAUCAAUGGGAUCAUGAAACCUGGUCUCAACGCCAUCCUGGGACCCACAGGUGGAGGCAAAUCUUCGUUAUUAGAUGUCUUAGCUGCAAGGAAAGAUCCAAGUGGAUUAUCUGGAGAUGUUCUGAUAAAUGGAGCACCGCGACCUGCCAAUUUCAAAUGUAAUUCAGGUUACGUGGUACAAGAUGAUGUUGUGAUGGGCACUCUGACGGUGAGAGAAAACUUACAGUUCUCAGCAGCUCUUCGGCUUGCAACAACUAUGACGAAUCAUGAAAAAAACGAACGGAUUAACAGGGUCAUUCAAGAGUUAGGUCUGGAUAAAGUGGCAGACUCCAAGGUUGGAACUCAGUUUAUCCGUGGUGUGUCUGGAGGAGAAAGAAAAAGGACUAGUAUAGGAAUGGAGCUUAUCACUGAUCCUUCCAUCUUGUUCUUGGAUGAGCCUACAACUGGCUUAGACUCAAGCACAGCAAAUGCUGUCCUUUUGCUCCUGAAAAGGAUGUCUAAGCAGGGACGAACAAUCAUCUUCUCCAUUCAUCAGCCUCGAUAUUCCAUCUUCAAGUUGUUUGAUAGCCUCACCUUAUUGGCCUCAGGAAGACUUAUGUUCCACGGGCCUGCUCAGGAGGCCUUGGGAUACUUUGAAUCAGCUGGUUAUCACUGUGAGGCCUAUAAUAACCCUGCAGACUUCUUCUUGGACAUCAUUAAUGGAGAUUCCACUGCUGUGGCAUUAAACAGAGAAGAAGACUUUAAAGCCACAGAGAUCAUAGAGCCUUCCAAGCAGGAUAAGCCACUCAUAGAAAAAUUAGCGGAGAUUUAUGUCAACUCCUCCUUCUACAAAGAGACAAAAGCUGAAUUACAUCAACUUUCCGGGGGUGAGAAGAAGAAGAAGAUCACAGUCUUCAAGGAGAUCAGCUACACCACCUCCUUCUGUCAUCAACUCAGAUGGGUUUCCAAGCGUUCAUUCAAAAACUUGCUGGGUAAUCCCCAGGCCUCUAUAGCUCAGAUCAUUGUCACAGUCGUACUGGGACUGGUUAUAGGUGCCAUUUACUUUGGGCUAAAAAAUGAUUCUACUGGAAUCCAGAACAGAGCUGGGGUUCUCUUCUUCCUGACGACCAACCAGUGUUUCAGCAGUGUUUCAGCCGUGGAACUCUUUGUGGUAGAGAAGAAGCUCUUCAUACAUGAAUACAUCAGCGGAUACUACAGAGUGUCAUCUUAUUUCCUUGGAAAACUGUUAUCUGAUUUAUUACCCAUGAGGAUGUUACCAAGUAUUAUAUUUACCUGUAUAGUGUACUUCAUGUUAGGAUUGAAGCCAAAGGCAGAUGCCUUCUUCGUUAUGAUGUUUACCCUUAUGAUGGUGGCUUAUUCAGCCAGUUCCAUGGCACUGGCCAUAGCAGCAGGUCAGAGUGUGGUUUCUGUAGCAACACUUCUCAUGACCAUCUGUUUUGUGUUUAUGAUGAUUUUUUCAGGUCUGUUGGUCAAUCUCACAACCAUUGCAUCUUGGCUGUCAUGGCUUCAGUACUUCAGCAUUCCACGAUAUGGAUUUACGGCUUUGCAGCAUAAUGAAUUUUUGGGACAAAACUUCUGCCCAGGACUCAAUGCAACAGGAAACAAUCCUUGUAACUAUGCAACAUGUACUGGCGAAGAAUAUUUGGUAAAGCAGGGCAUCGAUCUCUCACCCUGGGGCUUGUGGAAGAAUCACGUGGCCUUGGCUUGUAUGAUUGUUAUUUUCCUCACAAUUGCCUACCUGAAAUUGUUAUUUCUUAAAAAAUAUUCUUAAAUUUCCCCUUAAUUCAGUAUGAUUUAUCCUCACAUAAAAAAGAAGCACUUUGAUUGAAGUAUUCAAUCAAGUUUUUUUGUUGUUUUCUGUUCCCUUGCCAUCACACUGUUGCACAGCAGCAAUUGUUUUAAAGAGAUACAUUUUUAGAAAUCACAACAAACUGAAUUAAACAUGAAAGAACCCAAGACAUCAUGUAUCGCAUAUUAGUUAAUCUCCUCAGACAGUAACCAUGGGGAAGAAAUCUGGUCUAAUUUAUUAAUCUAAAAAAGGAGAAUUGAAUUCUGGAAACUCCUGACAAGUUAUUACUGUCUCUGGCAUUUGUUUCCUCAUCUUUAAAAUGAAUAGGUAGGUUAGUAGCCCUUCAGUCUUAAUACUUUAUGAUGCUAUGGUUUGCCAUUAUUUAAUAAAUGACAAAUGUAUUAAUGCUAUACUGGAAAUGUAAAAUUGAAAAUAUGUUGGAAAAAAGAUUCUGUCUUAUAGGGUAAAAAAAGCCACCGUGAUAGAAAAAAAAUCUUUUUGAUAAGCACAUUAAAGUUAAUAGAACUUACUGAUAUUCCUGUCUAGUGGUAUAAUAUCUCAGGAAUCUUGGCUGAGGGUUUGGAACUGUGGGUAGAGUAGAGGGCCAGGAGUCCAGUAAUAGAAUUCUUGCACCAUUUCUGGAACAUUCUAGCUCUGGGAGGUCACGUAACCUUCUUGGGGUAGUUCAGUGGUUUAGUGGUUUAUAAUCCAGGUGUGCGUCAGAAUCAUCUGAGGAACUUUGCUAAAAUACAAAAAUCUGGCCUAAGUAGCUCCAGAUCUACCUUCAUAAAGGAAUCUGACCACUCCUGGAUUUGGUAAUUUCCAAGUUCUGAAAAUUUUACUUAGGAUUUAAUAACUAUUAACAUCUGUCCCUACAUAGGUUUUCUUUCCUACUUAUAUACCUUAUGUUCUCUUCAUUCUAACCUUCAUCAGUAAUAGGGAAAUGUUUUAAUUUUAUUUUUUUAGUUGAAGGGUAAUGUACCAAAAAAUAUAGUUCAGUGAAUUAAAAUGAACACACAUGUGCAACCAUCAAUUCAGGUCAAGAAAUAGAAGAUUGUAGCACACAAAAGCCUACUCAGCCAUUCUCCCAGUCACUACUUCCUUCCUUACCCCUGGGUUAUUUUUGAAAUGACACUUGAUGUAUUUCCCUCUGUUGCUGUUAUGAGAACAUUGCUACAGCCAAGUGUUGUGUUUCUGUGUGCAUAGGUUGAUACUUAAUUAUCUCCCCACUUUUUAAUAAACUUUUAAUUUGGAAAUAAUUUUAGAUUGACAGAAAAGUUGCAAAGAUAGUGAGGAAAGUUCCUGUCUACUCUUUGCUCAGCUUCCCUUAAUGUUAACAUUUUAUAUAGCAAGAUGCAUUUGUCAAAGCUAACAAGUUAACAUUGGUACAAUCACUGUUAAUUAAACUGCACACAAUAUUCAGAUUUCACCACUUUUCCACUAAUAUUCUUUCAUUGUUCUAGGAUUCAAUUCAGGAGACCACAUUUCAUCUAGCCCUCUUUUUUAAAAGUAAAUACUUUUCAGCACUUACAGGAGUUAACUGAGCUGGGGCAUCAUGGUGUAUAGACGCCCUGACACUGGUCAUCUUGGAAUUCAUUUAGUUUGUCAGUGGGUGCCCUGACAUUCUGUCACAACAUCAAUUUGGGAACAUGGCAUUAUAUUUUUAUCUUUGAACUUUUUUCUUUUUGGAUGACAUUUGAUUAAUGCGUCAUCUUGGAACACAUUAUCUUUUUUCUUGGUUAUGUGAUCAGGAAGAUUAAUCAGUUUUUCCUGUUCUUGGUAUAAUUCCUGCUUUUCACAUACCUGUCCCUUACAGUUCUCUAUAUAUACCCUUCCCUUAUUACACAGAGAGAAAUAUCUAUCUAUACUUUUUACACAAAAUAUACUUCAAAAGAAACAAAACAGCCACAAUUAUUAACUUUUUAAAUAAAUGAGAAUUUAAUUAUAUCCUA